GACGAUGCGAACAACAUGGCGGCGGAAAGUGGUAGCGAUUUUCAGCAGAGACGUAGAAGGCGCCGGGACCCGGAGGAACCGGAAAAAACAGAACUCAGCGAAAGAGAGCUGGCAGUAGCAGUGGCGGUGUCCCAGGAGAACGAUGAGGAGAACGAAGAGCGCUGGGUUGGACCUUUACCUGUGGAGGCAACACUGGCCAAGAAGAGGAAAGCAGCCACAUGAAGUUGGAAUUUCGAACUCUUAUUUAGUCUUAGAGUUUGAAAGAGUCUAUCUUGAUAAUCUCCCCAGUGCAUCCAUGUAUGAGCGCAGUUACAUGCAUAGAGAUGUUAUCACCCAUGUGGUAUGCACCAAAACAGAUUUUAUUAUUACUGCCAGUCAUGAUGGACAUGUCAAGUUCUGGAAAAAAAUAGAAGAGGGAAUUGAAUUUGUUAAACAUUUUCGUAGUCACCUGGGAGUUAUUGAGAGUAUUGCAGUUAGCUCUGAGGGAGCAUUGUUCUGUUCUGUGGGUGAUGAUAAAGCAAUGAAGGUGUUUGAUGUAGUGAACUUUGACAUGAUCAACAUGCUGAAACUUGGCUAUUUUCCUGGACAGUGUGAGUGGAUCUAUUGCCCAGGGGAUGCAAUUUCUUCAGUUGCUGCUUCCGAAAAGAGUACAGGAAAAAUUUUCAUUUAUGAUGGCCGAGGAGAUAACCAGCCACUUCAUAUUUUUGACAAACUCCAUACAUCACCUCUUACUCAGAUACGGCUAAACCCAGUUUACAAAGCAGUAGUGUCUUCUGACAAAUCUGGGAUGAUUGAAUACUGGACUGGGCCUCCUCAUGAAUAUAAAUUCCCCAAAAAUGUGAACUGGGAAUAUAAAACUGACACUGAUUUAUAUGAAUUUGCCAAGUGUAAGGCUUAUCCAACCAGCGUAUGUUUUUCACCAGAUGGGAAGAAAAUAGCUACUAUUGGUUCUGAUAGAAAAGUUAGAAUUUUCAGAUUUGUAACUGGAAAACUCAUGAGAGUCUUUGAUGAAUCACUAAGCAUGUUUACUGAACUGCAACAGAUGAGGCAACAGUUACCAGACAUGGAAUUUGGCCGACGAAUGGCUGUAGAACGUGAGUUGGAGAAGGUUGAUGCUGUAAGAUUAAUUAAUAUAGUUUUUGAUGAAACUGGACACUUCGUGCUGUAUGGAACAAUGCUGGGCAUUAAAGUUAUAAAUGUAGAGACAAACCGGUGUGUGCGGAUUUUAGGCAAACAAGAAAAUAUUAGAGUGAUGCAAUUGGCUUUGUUCCAGGGGAUAGCCAAAAAGCAUCGUGCUGCAACUACUAUAGAAAUGAAAGCUUCUGAAAAUCCUGUUCUUCAGAAUAUUCAAGCUGACCCAACAAUAGUCUGUACAUCAUUCAAAAAGAAUAGAUUUUAUAUGUUUACCAAACGAGAACCAGAAGAUACGAAAAGUGCAGAUUCUGAUCGAGAUGUUUUUAAUGAGAAACCUUCUAAAGAAGAAGUCAUGGCAGCUACUCAAGCUGAAGGACCUAAACGAGUUUCGGACAGUGCCAUUAUCCACACCAGCAUGGGAGACAUUCACACCAAACUUUUUCCUGUUGAGUGCCCUAAGACAGUGGAAAACUUCUGUGUUCACAGCAGAAAUGGUUAUUAUAAUGGGCAUACAUUUCACCGUAUAAUUAAGGGCUUUAUGAUUCAGACUGGAGAUCCAACAGGUACUGGUAUGGGAGGAGAAAGCAUAUGGGGAGGAGAAUUUGAAGAUGAAUUUCAUUCAACAUUACGACAUGACAGGCCAUACACACUCAGCAUGGCUAACGCGGGAUCAAAUACUAAUGGAUCCCAGUUUUUCAUAACGGUAGUACCAACGCCUUGGCUUGAUAAUAAGCAUACAGUAUUUGGACGAGUGACUAAAGGAAUGGAAGUUGUACAGAGGAUCUCCAACGUCAAAGUCAAUCCCAAAACAGAUAAGCCCUAUGAGGAUGUCAGCAUCAUAAAUAUUACUGUCAAGUAAAAUAAGAUUUGUUUUAAUGUACUUGCAAAUAAAAAUACAAUAUUAAACAGAUUAUUUUACAUUAGGAAGCUUAGGACUUGCUGAAUAUACAGAUCAUGUUUCAAAGAUACAGUAUUUUUGUAUUUUUUAUUAAAGGCUAUUUUUUAAAAAUUA